AACGGCAGUGGCACUCACCCGGCUCGCGCGGCCCCGGCGCCCCACGCGCGCGCGUCGUUCUCCCGCCCGCUCGCUCCCCGGCGCUCACACCUGAGCUCACUCGCGCACGCCCGCCCGGCCCGAGAACCGCGCCGCCGCCUCGGCCCCGCGGAAGCCCCGCCGCGUCAUGUCUUCGCCUCCCGAAGGGAAACUAGAGACUAAAGCUGGACACCCGCCCGCCGUGAAAGCUGGUGGAAUGCGAAUUGUGCAGAAACACCCACAUACAGGAGACACCAAAGAAGAGAAAGACAAGGAUGACCAGGAAUGGGAAAGCCCCAGUCCACCUAAACCCACUGUGUUCAUCUCUGGGGUCAUCGCCCGGGGUGACAAAGAUUUCCCCCCGGCGGCUGCGCAGGUGGCUCACCAGAAGCCGCAUGCCUCCAUGGACAAGCAUCCUUCCCCAAGAACCCAGCACAUCCAGCAGCCACGCAAGUGAGCCUGGAGUCCACCAGCCUGCCCCAUGGCCCCGGCUCUGCUGCACUUGGUAUUUCCCUGACAGAGAGAACCAGCAGUUUCGCCCAAAUCCUACUCUGCUGGGAAAUCUAAGGCAAAACCAAGUGCUCUGUCCUUUGCCUUACAUUUCCAUAUUUAAAACUAGAAACAGCUCCAGCCCAAACCUUGUUUAUGGGGAGUCUGGUUGGAUGUCAUUUGAGGAUCAUUGUGCCCCUAGAGGUGCCAUUAGCAGAAUUUGCCAAGAUCCGAGAAAAAUUUUAGCUUUAGUUCUAUUUCAGCAGUCACCUGACGUCCUUGUCUAUGGUCUUAAAAACAAGAAGGCACACAUUUGAGAAGAUGAGAUUAAGGUUAGGAGAAAACCUCAGUCAUUGCAUGCUUUUUAGUAUGGGCCAAUAAAAUCUCAACACCUGUGGGAGAGUAAGAACUAAGGGAAUGAGUUUGGGCGGCCCCUCAUAAAGGACCUUAGAGGCAGGGAACAGCAAUGCCAAAUUUCCCUCUCUCGUGAGAUGGGGGAUCCUGUGCAGGCUGAUGAGGCACCCAUGAGAAAAGCCGAAAAAGCAUGCAUCUUAGAAAUAGCCCCUCAAUUCCAGGAGUCAACAUGCCAAAGAAUGAGGCUGGAGACAGGUAGCUCCGAGGGAGGACUUCUGGCAUGAGAUCUCGGCACGGCAAGCCCAGCAUCGCCUCAGCCCAGACAGGCUCCACCAGGAGAUCAAGCAAGGGCUGCCUUUCAGGAGUCACCUCCUGAGCCACUUCAGAGUUCUGGAAGUGACCACGGACCAGGGUGGAGGAAUAGACUUCUAGUUCAUUCUGGGACACUUGAGCCAGAGAGUUGAAAGCUUGGAAAGACCAGAUAAGAAACCUGCCCUUUGUCUCCCUAGGGACAUGAGACACCACAUUCCAUUUGUGCUAGAAAAACCUAUCCACUGAUGAGUCUAACUGUUCCAAACGCCUCCCACCUGGUGUGCACAGCUGCCUGGGUCCAUUGUCACUUGGGUGCAUCAGGUUGUCCUCCGAUUUUUAGAUGAGUUUCCUGUCUAGAGAUGUCCUAGUCUGCUCACUGGCUGGUGGCAGUAGGGUACCCUGCGUCCUCGAAAAGCCAGAGGGUUCACCUAGUCAGACGAAACUCCAGAACAGUGCUUGUGGAGGGCCUGACUGUCCUGCUCACCCACAGCCGAUCUGCUGCAGGUCAGCAACUGUGUCGUGAGCAGCUGCCAACCACCAGCCUUUCUGGUGCUGUUCUCCAGUUCACGUCUGCCAGCUGGUGAGGGCAGAGGCAGACCUGGUCAGACCCAGCGCCCCUCCUCCCUGAGGGAGCAUGGCACAGCCUCACACUUGAAAGACGGUGUUUGGUUUCCCAUCUAAUCAACUUAAGGGAAGCCGGCAUGUACCCUUCAAGGCCCUGUCACCACCUAUUUCCUGAUCAGUUGGUAUAAACUGAGGGUGGCUUUUAGAGACCCAGACUUGGUUGGCAGCGCUGCCAUGGAACACCCCAGCAAGCACCUCCCAGCCUGCCUUUCGGAGCAGCACCCAGGAGGGGAUGCCGCGCUCCAGCAACACCAGGUCAGGCCUGUGCAGACCCCUGCCCUGCCGCUGCAGAAAUCCAGAAGCAUCCUUAAUGCUUCUCAGUCUUCAGCCAGAGGGAGGGCUGUUAUUUCCAGAGGUGCGCUUUUUAUGUACUUUUAGCUAGAUGUGGCAUGCAUCUGUGAGCUUUAGAUCAUUAAAUCCAAAAUGUUUGCCUAAAUGAGUUUAUCAGUUGUUAACUUCAAGAAUAUUAAAUGAUUUAUAAUAAAGCUCCUGCAUUUCUCUCCA